AGCAUUUCCACUUUCGUCAGGUACUGGAGAGGGCUGCCGGCCGGAUGCCAGGGCAGAGGGGCAGGGCGGACGGCUAGGAGUUCAAGAAACAUCCUGGUCUGAGGGAAAGGCUGCAGCCUGCACCGCCAUGAAUAAGCUUUUCAGCUUCUGGAAGAGGAAGAAUGAGACCCGCAGCCAGGGCUACAACCUUCGAGAAAAGGAUUUAAAGAAACUUCACAGAGCUGCUUCAGUCGGGGAUUUGAAGAAGCUGAAGGAAUACCUUCAGAUCAAGAAAUAUGAUGUAAAUAUGCAGGACAAAAAAUACAGAACACCUUUGCACCUAGCCUGUGCUAAUGGACAUACAGAUGUUGUACUUUUCCUAAUUGAGCAACAAUGCAAAAUAAAUGUCCGGGAUAGUGAAAACAAAUCCCCAUUGAUUAAGGCAGUACAGUGUCAAAAUGAGGAUUGUGCUACUAUUCUUCUAAACUUUGGUGCAGACCCAGAUCUGAGGGAUAUUCGUUAUAAUACUGUUCUUCACUAUGCUGUUUGUGGUCAAAGUUUGUCAUUAGUUGAAAAACUGCUUGAAUACGAAGCUGAUCUUGAAGCGAAAAAUAAGGAUGGGUAUACUCCACUAUUAGUUGCCGUUAUUAACAAUAAUCCAAAAAUGGUAAAAUUUCUUCUGGAGAAAGGGGCUGAUGUGAAUGCUUCAGAUAAUUAUCAAAGAACAGCCCUUAUUCUUGCUGUCAGUGGUGAACCACCAUGUUUAGUAAAGCUUCUUCUUCAGCAAGGUGUGGAAUUAUGUUACGAAGGUAUUGUGGAUUCACAGCUGAGGAAUAUGUUUAUUUCCAUGGUUUUACUGCAUAGAUACCCACAAUUCACUGCGAGCCAUGGAAAGAAGAAACAUGCUAAAUAGACACCUUAUUCUUGGCACUACAUGUGACUAAAGGAAGAUAUGGAACCCAUUUCUACAAUUUCUUUGCCGCUUCCUUGAAUUGGAAAAAUGUACUUUGAAAGAACCGUUAAGUGAACUAUUAUAAUAUUUUUGCUGACUACCCAGUUGAAGAAAAGUUUGUUAAUUGGAUGGGAUUUUUUUUUUUUCACGUUAGAAGACAUGAAGAAAUUUUAAAAGAUAAACAUCUAUAUUGUGAACCAUCAGCUGAAAAGAUAAAUUUGUGUUCAAUAUAUAGGCAGAAAAAAAUUUGUGUCAAAAUGUUGAAUGGAAUAAUAAUGAGGAAACUGUGUUAGGCAUGUAUUAAAACAUUUAAAUAAAAUAAAAAUACAUUUCAGCUACAAAGUGAAGGAAAACAUUAUAAAUAAUCCUGUAUAAAUCAAAA